AGCUUUUCCUUUCUGCCACCGCCUUGUCCAAGAUGGCGGACCUCCACCGCCAGCUGCAGGAGUACCUGGCGCAGGGGAAAGCUGGCGGCCCGGCGGCCGCGGAGCCGCUGCUCGCCGCGGAGAAGGCGGAGGAGCCCGGGGACCGGCCGGCGGAGGAGUGGCUGGGCCGCGCGGGCUUGCGCUGGACGUGGGCGCGGAGCCCUGCGGAGUCGGCAGCGGCCGGCCUGACGUGCCUCCCGAGCGUGACGCGCGGGCAGCGGCUGGCGGCGGGCGGCGGGUGCCUGCUGCUGGCUGCACUGUGUUUCGGCCUAGCCGCGCUCUACGCACCGGUGUUGCUGCUGCGCGCGCGCAAGUUCGCGCUGCUCUGGUCACUGGGCUCGGCGCUGGCGUUGGCGGGAAGCGCGCUGCUGCGGGGCGGCGCGGCGUGCGGACGCCUGCUGCGCUGCGAAGAAGCGCCGUCCCGGCCCGCGCUGCUCUACAUGGCAGCGCUGGGCGCCACGCUGUUCGCCGCGCUGGGCCUUCGCAGCACGCUGCUCACGGUGCUGGGCGCGGGCGCGCAGGUGGCCGCGCUGCUGGCCGCGCUGGUUGGGCUGCUGCCCUGGGGCGGCGGCACCGCGCUGCGCCUCGCACUGGGUCGCCUGGGCCGCGGCGCCGGCCUCGCCAAGGUGCUGCCCGUGUGAGGACCUCGCGCCCUCGCCGCUGGGGAAGUACGCGGAGCCAGCGCCGUCGGAGACCGCGCCGGCCGAGCUGAGGACUGCACGCCGCUGUGCGGAAGCCCGUGGCGAAGGCCCUGCCCUAACAGCCUGCGAGUCUAAUCCGGGAGCGGCUGCUGCCAGCGGAGGCGACAGCAGCGUUGGGAGCUCCUCGAUGUCAGCUUUUUGUGCUGGACUUGGCACACGCUCUGAAAACUGAGAUUUUGUCAUUGAACUGGUGACAGGAUGUGAGACGGUUAUUAGAAGUUGCUUUCGAAGUAACUGUGGUCUUAGGUUCGGCUGAGUAAAGAAAAAGGAUUUUUCUUCGAGUUAGCUGCUCUUGUGAUUUUUCUCAGGCUGUUUUGUCAUUUUAAAAUCCAGUGGUAGAUGUAGCUUAGCGACGGUAGUUUUUUGUUUUGGCUAUACUAAGACUUGGAAAUUAUUCUCUCCAGUGUCAGCGAAUCCAGAAGGGUAUCAGAUUAAACACCGAAUUCAGCCACUGGACUUUUAAAAGUACUUAAGAUGGUUUAUCUCGGGUUUUUUCUUCAGUUAACAAAAUCAUAAAUAUGGUGCCUUAUAACAUGAAAGGAAAAUUAGUUGUGUAUUUCACGACGAAAGCGACGGACCAAAAGAAAUUUCCUGCCCCAAGAAGCAUGGGAUCCAGGAAGGGGCGCGUAGAUGCUUAACGGUCUCUUCGGAAAUCCUGCAAAUAGAAAGAUAAUUCUAGAUCCGGAAUACCUGUAUCUGGUGGAAACCAUGGAUUUCUACAAGCUCGAAUUAUUCCUCAUUGUAUAGCCUGCUUUGUAAACUAGUUUACAAUUUGCAGGCUGAUCUUAAGAUUUUUUUAUAUCUAAUUGCUGCUGCCUUCAUUUUAGGUUCAGCAGUUACUUUUAACUACCUUAAUUUAUUGCCAGAAGGUAUGAGCCUAACAUUCUGAUGAGUCCAGAAAACUACGUUUUGUCAGUAGCAAUACACUAGGAAGUAAAAUAUAUUUAGAAUUUAAACAUUGUGUGCCAGUGGUCCUCGCGCUUGACUGCACAUCAGUUACUUGAAGAGCCACACCUCAGAUCAAUGCAGUCAGAACCUGGGAAGUAGGUCCCAGACAUCAGGACCUUUUUAAAGCUCCCCAAGUGAUUCUACGUUCCCCAAGUUUGAGGACCACUUUUCUGUGCAUUGGCUUGCACAAUUUGAAAGUAAUGCUUUUCCUGAGCUGGAUCCCAGUGUUGCCUUAACAGGGUGUCUGUCGUGCCGCAGUAGAGCACUGCUGCUUCCUCCAACCCCAAAAUUUAUGUUCCUAAGUAAGUCAGGUCCCUAAGCCCCGUCCCAAGAAGUGACACAAGUGGCCAACAUCCACACUGUAGGCUUGCAGGCUACCCGCCCUGAGAUUUGGUAAAGAACACUGCCUUGUUCCCCAUCAGUAAACAAGGUUACCUACCUCAGGAGGCUGCUUGUGAGAGAGCAAAUGCAGUAUCUUCAGAAUGAUUUAUUUUUUUAAUUAAUUGUAAAGACUUGUGCCAUUGGCUGCUCUUUCUAGUCCCCUAAAUUUCUGUUCUAGUUUUAAAUUUCUCUAGAACUUGCAAUAGUUGGGGGUUUUAUAAUGAUGUUUUACAAUGUUUAUUUCUUAAAUAAAAACUUAAAAAUUCAACAUUUCUCAGCUGGUGGCUCACACCUGUAAUCCCAGCAUUUUGGGAGGCCAAGGCGGGAGGAUCACUUGAGGCCAGGAGUUCAAGACCAGCCUGGGCAACACAGUUAAACCCCAUCGCCACAGAAAAUCUUCAAAAAAUUUGCCAGAUAUGGUGGCACACAACUGUGAUCCCAGCUACUUGGGGUGGGGCUGAGGUGGGAAGAUCACUUGAGCCCAGGAGGUUGAGGCUGCAGUGAACUGUGAUCACACCACUGCACCACAGCCUAGGCAACAGCGAGACCUUGUCUCAAAAAUUUUUUCUCAAAUCAAACAUCAUUGAAAAUCUACUUUUUAUAAGCUUCAAAUCACAACAUCUAGUAUGUAUGCUGACAGUGAUGUUUUUAAAUGCCAUAUAUAUUUAAUAAGUAUAAUGUAGAGGUUUAUUGUUUAAAUGAAUUCACUCUCAAAAUGUGAUCUGUCAAGUCCAGUAGAGCUUCAAGGUAAAAUGAAAAUUUUUAAAUGUGAUCUGGUUAUCUGCUUACUGAGAUACUAUGUUUCUAAAGUUAAAGCCCAAAAUAAUGAAAAUUUUUCCACUAGAAUCUCAGGGAAAAAAAGUCUAAUCUUGAUAUGGGUUUGGUCUCUGGAUCCGGUUUUAGCUUCAUGAAAUUUGAUUACAGUUUCUCUCUCUUUAAGCUAUACCAGUUGGGGGUGAGUGAAGAAAUACCCAUAACCUAAAGCAAUCUUGAGCCUCCUAAUAGCAUGUUUAUGGUGGAGCGCUGAUUAAAUAAGCUGUAAUUUCAAAGUUAAAAAAAAAAUAGUCUCUAGAUUCUAACACUGAAAAGCAGUGUAUAUGGCUGACAUUUUCUCACUCCACAGAAAUCAAUUAGCUUUUGCUGUUUUUUACAUUCAUAGAGAACCAGUUAAAUUUUCAUAUCCUGUUAAACUAUAUCAGUAUGCCUUUUCUAAGCAACCAUUGAAACUUCCAGCACCAGCGGCCAGGUACUGUGGCUCAGAUCUGCAAUCCCAGCACUUUGGGAGGCCACAGCAGGUGGACCGCUUGAGCCCAGGAGUUUGAAACCAGCAUAGACAAAGUGGUGAAACUCCAUCUCUACAAAAAACACACACACAAAAAAUUAGCUGGGCAUGGUGGCAUAUGCCUGUAGUCCUAGCUACUAGGGAGGCUGAGGCAGGGUCAAAGCUGAAGUGAGCCGUGAUUGCACCACUGCACUCCUGGCUGGGUGACAGAGCAAGACUCUGUCAAAAAAGGAAAAGAAAAAAAGAAACUUCCAGCACCACUAAAUUUGCCAAAUAAAUUUGACUGAUGCCAAAACUGAAGCUGCCAAUGUAAUGAAAUGUUAAGGUGGCCAUAGGACAGUCCUUUUAAUAAAAGCUUCCAUGUAAAACCAAAAUAAAGGUCAGUAUAGAAAGUA